CGGGUGGGGAGGUGGGGUCCGGGUGUGCGCCGCGGCGCUGGCUGCGAAGGCAGUGGCCGAGGCGGGCUCCCUCUGGGCCGUGCCCGGCCUGGCUAACAAAGCCGCCGCGGCCUCUGUUGUGUGAUGGUGUCUUUUAUGAAUAAUCAAAAGCAGCAAAAGCCAACGCUAUCAGGCCAGCGUUUUAAAACUAGAAAAAGAGAUGAAAAAGAGAGGUUUGACCCUACUCAGUUUCAAGACUGUAUUAUUCAAGGCUUAACUGAAACCGGUACUGAUUUGGAAGCAGUAGCUAAGUUUCUUGAUGCUUCUGGAGCAAAACUUGAUUACCGUCGAUAUGCAGAAACACUCUUUGACAUUCUGGUGGCUGGUGGAAUGCUGGCCCCAGGUGGUACACUGGCAGAUGACAUGAUGCGUACAGAUGUCUGCGUGUUUGCAGCCCAAGAAGAUCUAGAGACCAUGCAAGCAUUUGCUCAGGUUUUUAACAAGUUAAUCAGGCGCUACAAAUACCUGGAGAAAGGUUUUGAAGAUGAAGUAAAAAAGCUGCUGCUGUUCUUGAAGGGUUUUUCAGAGUCGGAGAGGAACAAGCUAGCUAUGUUGACUGGUGUUCUUCUGGCUAAUGGAACACUUAAUGCAUCCAUUCUUAAUAGCCUUUAUAAUGAAAAUUUGGUUAAAGAAGGAGUUUCAGCAGCUUUUGCUGUGAAGCUCUUUAAAUCAUGGAUAAAUGAAAAAGAUAUCAAUGCAGUAGCUGCAAGUCUUCGGAAAGUCAGCAUGGAUAACAGACUGAUGGAACUCUUUCCUGCCAAUAAGCAAAGUGUUGAACACUUCACAAAAUAUUUUACUGAGGCAGGCUUGAAAGAGCUUUCAGAAUAUGUUCGGAAUCAGCAAACCAUCGGAGCUCGUAAGGAGCUCCAGAAAGAACUUCAAGAACAGAUGUCCCGUGGUGAUCCAUUUAAGGAUAUAAUUUUAUAUGUCAAGGAGGAGAUGAAAAAAAACAACAUCCCAGAGCCAGUUGUCAUCGGAAUAGUCUGGUCAAGUGUAAUGAGCACUGUGGAAUGGAACAAAAAAGAGGAGCUUGUAGCAGAGCAAGCCAUCAAGCACUUGAAGCAAUACAGCCCUCUACUUGCUGCCUUUACUACUCAAGGUCAGUCUGAGCUGACUCUGUUACUGAAGAUUCAGGAGUAUUGCUAUGACAACAUUCAUUUCAUGAAAGCCUUCCAGAAAAUAGUGGUGCUUUUUUAUAAAGCUGAAGUCCUGAGCGAGGAGCCCAUUUUGAAGUGGUAUAAAGAUGCACAUGUUGCAAAGGGGAAGAGUGUUUUCCUUGAGCAAAUGAAAAAGUUUGUAGAAUGGCUCAAAAAUGCUGAAGAAGAAUCUGAAUCUGAAGCUGAAGAAGGUGACUGAAUUUUGAAACUACACCCUCAGUAAAGCAAACAGGAGUUGUAGAUAAAAUGUCAUGUCUCAUGUGUCCUGGUUCUUACAUCUUCCUACCUCCCUGUAUCAAGCAUGAUAUAAGGGCUUUCAUGGCAAAUUUUAUUUUAACUGUUUCUAUGGUUGCUGGAAAUGUUGGGUUUAGUUUCUAAAACCAUGUUUUAAGUAGCUACAGGAGCUAUAGAUUUGAAUCUAAUGUUGCAUUAGUCUUUUCAGUUAUCUUCUACCUCCUGUAUUUUCUACUGUAAUAAUGUAAUUUAAGGCCUUCCACAAUGAACAGUUCACUUUAUUCCCUGGGUUUUCUAUAAACAGUUUUAAGGAUAUGAUUUGGUUAAAAAAUAAUUUGUUAUAAAAAUUCUGUUUGCAAAUUAAACUGGAAAAGUAUCCAGAGUCUCAAAAGGCAAUGAUUUGUGAGAUAAUAUGGCAUGCCCGGAGCCCUGCUCAUCAAUGAAAAACCCAUAUGUAAUAAUCGAAUUCAUUUAACAUGAAUCUUGAGUACGUGGACCAUUGCUUGCAUGUUAACUUUUUGUUUUGUUUUGUUUUGUUUUGUUUUGCAUUUUUAACUCCAGAUAUCCUAAAGCUCAAUUGUUUGGUCUCUGGUUUUCAUCCUUAGAGAAGCCAUGGAGAACAGACUUGAAAAGUUUAGGAAAUCAUAAUGUGGCAGAGGUGGUGGGAAGAAGAAAGUUGAGCUUUUUCCCCUUGAGAAACUUCUGCAUUUAGUUUCUAUCUUUCCAGGCAAAACAAAUGGGUAUUCUUUUCAUACAACCAUUUUCAAAUGAACCUUAGAAAAGUCUUAACAUUUAAGGUAUUUUAUGCACAGAAUACACUUAGAUUGAUAGGAAAGAACUCGUAAUGGAGUUUGAGUAAAGAAAAUGACUGAUGUACUAAACCCAGUAAAAAUUGUUGAAAAUGUUAAAGGUCAGCAUGUUCUAAUUGGGAAUCUAGAUAUAGCUUAGAUUUCCUAUUGGCUUAGAGUAUUUGCUAUAACAAAUGAAGUGCAAUGACAAUUAUAUAUUCCUACUCGGUCAUACUGGACUGGCUUCGUUCUCUUAAUAUACUCAGUAAUGACUCAAGCCUCUGGCUAUUAACAUACCCUAGUUGCCGUUUUUUAAUUGCCAUGAGCCAAAUACUUCUUGGUAUACAAUUGAUCCAUUUAUUUUAAUGGCUGCCUUUUCAUUUUCAUCUUUUCUUGCUGCUACCCAUCUAUGUAUGUAGUCAUUGGGGGGAAAAUGUAGCCACAUUUUUUAUGGGAAGACUUUGUGUUAAAAGUGAACAUUUUGAAGGUUUUUAACUGGUGAAACUAGCCUGGAAUAAUGCCACCAGAGACUGAGUGGAAAUCGCCCCUUUUGAAGGUGCCAUUCUUAUGAGCCAAAAGUUUGUCAUUUAAAAGUUCAUUUUGAGGGAAUAACAUGUAAUAUAAUUUGAAAUAAAGGUAUAGUAACCUUAAAAAGAACAUUAUAACUGAUUGUUGUGAAUGGGGUGAAUUUGUUAAAAUGAGUAACUUUGAUAAAGUUUUUCAUGCACAGGCAAAAUGUAUUCACUAGAUUUCUACGUAGUGAUCUGCUUUUACUUUGUAAUUUGUAGUUCUCAAAAGACUUUUUUUUAAAAAAAUAAAGUCCAUACUUACACUUAGGCUUUAUACAUCAGUCUUUUUUUUUUUAAAUUCCAUGUUAAUACCUAGUGGUAUUGUAUGUUGUGUGUUCAGAUGUCUUUACUGUAUCUGUAUACCAUUAAGUAAUAAUUAGACUCCCAAACUGUAAACCACCUACACAGAAUUCUGGUGUAGCUAAAACUACAUUAAUAUUUCUACAACCAAUUCAUUGCAUGUUUCUUCCAUACAAAGUGUGCCAUUUUAUACUGUGUAUAGUGAAAAAGUGUGUCAUCUUCCAGAACUACAUUAUUAUCUUUGAUCGUAGUUUGUUUCUUCAUAAUGACACUGUAGUGUUUACUUAGUAGAACAUUAUAGUAAGUGGAUAUCACUUGUGACAGUAAUAGUGUAAAGAAAGGGAAUGCUUUAUAAAAAGAUUGCAGAUUCCAUUCCAUAUAAAAAGAUUCCAUUCUGAAUCUUAAGUGGUAAUUUUAGAAUUCAGGUGCCAGUGCCAGCCUAUGGCCUCAAGUAUGUAAUUCUUAAUAUAGAUGUUAAAUUGUACUUUUAAUUAUGAUUGGAUAAAUGUUUUUUCUAACUGUCAGUUUCUAAGGCUGUCUCCUUAGAAACUAAAUGAGUUUUUAGAGCUGGUUGUAAGUUUCUUAGCCUUACUCUGUGAGUUAUAGAUGUUAUUUCAUUCUAUAUAUAGAUGUUUAUUCCAUUCUUAUUUAAAAAAAAAAACCUCCAUAUACCAAAAAUGCUACAGGAUAUUUUGAAAUAGCAUAUUUUAGUUAGGGGAAAUGCAUGUGACCAAGAGGUUGGACUUCUAAUUCAGUUUUUCAAAAGCUUUUUUCCAUUAUCAUACCCCCAGCCUUUUUAGGCUUUUUUUUUUUUUUUUUUGAGACGGAGUCUCGCUCUGUCACCAGGCUGGAGUGCAGUGGCGCGAUCUUGGCUCACUGCAAGUUCCGCCUCCCGGGUUCACGCCAUUCUCCUGCCUCAGCCUCCCGAGUAGCUGGGACUACAGGCGCCCGCCACCAUGCCCGACUAAUUUUUUUGUAUUUUUAGUAGAGACGAGGUUUCACCGGAUUAGCGAGGAUGGUCUCAAUCUCCUGACCUUGUGAUCCACCCGCCUCAGCCUCCCAAAGUGCUGGGAUUAUGGGCUUGAGCCACCGCGCCCAGCUAGACUUUUUUCUAAUAGAGUCCCCCAUAAAUUUUAUUACCAUAGAUACGCUGUGUAUGUACUGUUUCUGUGCUUUGUACAUGAAAAGAGUAAAAUGUUUUUGUUUUUGUUUUGGAGACAGUCUCACUCUGUUACCUGGGCUGGAGUGCAAUGGCAUGAUCUCAGCUCACUGCAAUCUCUGCCUCCUGGGUUCAAGCGAUUCUCUUGCUUCAGCCUCCUGAGUAGCUGGGAUUACAGGCGGCCACCACCACCCCUGGCUAAUUUUUGUAUUUUUAGUAGAGGUUUCACCACGUUGAUCAGGCUGGUCUCAAACUCCUGACCUCGUGGUCUGCCUGCCUUGGCCUCCCAAAGUGCUGGGAUUACAGGCGUGAGCCACCAUGCCCAACCAAUUUUUUUUUUUUAAAUCCUUGGUAGUGAUUGACCCCCAUUGAGAAUGCAUGCUCUAAUAUUUUUUAAAAGGGAAGAAGACCUAGUGAUAGACCUUUGCAUUGGCAGGCAUGUCUUUAUGUUUAUACAGUGAAGUAGUAUUUUUUCUGUCAGGGUCAAUAGAAAGUAGACGAAAUUCAUUUUCAGCCAAUCUUUCACCAGUUGUGCUUUGUUCCUUACCCCACCACAGGCAACAGACAAAGCAUUUCCUGCUGUCUUUCAAGGUCUUAACAGAUUCUUUCUUGAUUAUAAAUGUAUUACUAAGUAGAAUCAUUUGGGUUCUUUCUAUAAAAAUCAGUGAAAAUCCUCUAGAUGAAUGAAUUAAAGUUGUAGGCAUAACACUGAUAAACCUCUGCUCUCAUACUGAAGUAGGCUGCUUGCAGGAACUGACAACUAUUGGUUGGCUUUAAAUGUAAUGUAGAUGCCAAAGUUUUAGUGUACAGUGUUACUUAAAUUACCAAAUUACCUUUGUACAAAUAUUCCUCAGAUGCUGUCUACAGGUGCCAUAUAAAAUAGGUUGAUAAGUAUUUGCAAAUUCUGGUAAAUUGCCUUGCUAUGAUUUUUCAUGCUCAGUAUUAGUCCUCUAGUAUCAAUACGAAGUUUUUCUAUUCCCCAGCCUACUAAGGCCUACAGGUUAAAAUACCAGGAAUAAAAAGGUUUUCAGUGGACUUGAUUUAAGUGGAAUCUGGAUGAUGUGACAAGUACCUUUGUCUUUGGAGUAAUGAGUUUAUAAUUGGCUUUUGUCCAAAAACUCUUAAGUGGAUUAAUAUCUGAACAAUCUUAGACAUAAUUAUAUGAAACUGGAUCAGAAAGGCUUUCUGACUCCUUUCUCUUCACUUUUUUCUCCCAGCUUAACUAGAGGCAAUUAACAGUCAUUUCAAAUCUAAUUAUUUUUAUUUUCCAGUGUACUUAUCAUCCUUUCAUCUUUAUGCUAGGAGUAUAGUCUCAGUUCUUAAUGAGUUGAUGGGAUGAAGAUAUAGAUAGAUAGAUAGAUAGAUAGAUAGAUAGAUAUUUUUUUUUUUUUUUUUUUUUUUUUUUUUUUUUUUGAGACAGAGUCUCGCUCUGUCGCCCAGGCGGGAGUGCAGUGGCACAAUCUCGGCUCACUGCAAGCUCCGCCUUGGGGGUUCACACCAUUCUCCUGUCUCAGCCUCCUAGCUGGGAUUACAGGCGCCCACCAACCAAGCCCGGCUAAGGUAUUUUUAAAUGUACUCAAUCACUGUCAUUUUAGUAACCUUGAAUCAGAACCUCAGUUGUUAAAGGCUUAACUGCUUGUGGCAACUACUAUAGUGCUCUAGUGGGGACAGUGGUUAAAAUCUGCAGAAUCCCUUGCUUUGUCAUCUUAUCCAGAAGGACUGAUAGCUUGUUAAACUGUGGUAUGAUUAGAAUGUUGGUGGUUGUGUAGUGCAUUUGGGGUGCUACAACGUUAAUCAAAUAUAAUUGAGCUGUUCUGUUUCCAGUCAGUGUAACCAUUUAAAAAUACCUUGGCAAAACAAGCUAGGAGCUAGUUCAUGCUAAUAUUCUUAAGGACAAAAAUAGUUUACAGCUUUUUUUUUUUUAAUCUGAAAUCCUGAAGGCUAUGCUUAAAAGUUAGAGAUAAACCUGUUGGAAAUAAGUGAUUCAUUUAUAGACUGAAGCCUCUAUGACUUCAAAAAGAUACUCAACAGUCUCUGGCAUUUGAAGAACAAAAUAUUUUCUCUGUAAAUACACCUCAUUUCCAUUCUAGUUAGGAGCAAUGGCGCCCAGGACGGCACACAGAAUGGAGAAAACUGGAUAGCUGGUAACUCAUUUAGCUCUUGGCACUCUAAAAAACCUCAAAUACAGCCAUCCAAGCCAGUAAUUCUAUUGCUGCGUUAUUUCUGUGUUUAACUGUGAAACUUGCUUCUUGUCUGUACCCUUGAAAUGGAAUAAAAUUUCAUGAGACUCCUUGUUAAUGUAGAGAAAA